AGGGGCCGGAGUGACUCCGGACUGAGAGGGCCAGGCGCCCAGGACCCCAUCGAGGGGUCCGGGGAGCCUGGGGUAUCCCCAAAGGCGGGGUCCGGGGAGCACCGGGCCCUUGGAUGAGGAGCUGGUUGGAGGCCUGGGUCCUGCCCAGUGGGAGGGGGACGAUAGGUGCUGGAAGCCCGGAUGCCCGCCUGGGAGGAGACCCUCUCGGAGCCUUGGCGGGAGAGCAAGAGUACAGAGUGGGUUCUUCUGAGGAGAGCAGAGUCCAGCUUAUCCCGAGGGGCGCGGUAGAGGCCUCGGCCACUCAGAACAAGGGAAAAAAGGGCAGGUUUUUUCCAAAGGCAGGGAAGGAAGAGGAGCUCUAAGGGGAAGUGAGCAGGCCCAGGUCUCCCCACAGAUGAGCGCGUGGUAGGAAGACUCCUAGAGCCUCCUGAAGUACGAAAGAGCAGCGUCCAAACCUGAGGGGAUGGAAGGUGUCUAGGUGCCUCUUGAUGUCUAGGUGGAGAACAAAGUAACCCGCUCGGUCAGGGGAUGGAGAAACCUAUCUUUUUGAGAGAAGCAGAGAUCGUUGAGGAAAGAUGCUUAAGGUGUUCCCGCUUUCUGAAAUGACAGGAAUUGGCCAGGUGUUAUCUAAUUGAGGGGCAGGAGAGAUGAAGGCAAAAUCUCAACCCGAGGGUCUUUGGAGGAUGAUCCACAAGACAAGAGGGUGAAGUCUUGACCUAGACAGCAGAGCAGGCGCAGCCCUGGAUUCUCUCAAGAUGAGAGAAAUCUCAAAACCACUUCCUAGUAGACACAGAUGGGGCCUUGAUUGGUGUCUGUUUAGGCCAAUCAAGACGGGUUUUAGGAAAAGAGACUGUCAGACAUAAUUCUAGUCUUGAGGGAUUAUCUUCUUCCUCCUUGCCUCUUCUAAUAGUUACCAAAGUGCAUUUGGGGACCCUUUUUAUUUAUUUAUUUAUUUAUUUGUUUUUUGAGACGGAGUCUCACUCUAUCGCCCAGGCUGGAGUGGUGGCUCACUGCAACUUCCGCCUCCUGGGUUCAAACGAUUCUCCUGCCUCAGCCUCCCGAGUAGCUGGGACUACAGGCGCGUGCCACCACACCAGCCAAUUUUGUUGUUGUUGUUGUUGUUGUUUGAGACGGAGUUUCACUCCUGUUGCCCAGACUGGAGUGCAAUGGCGCGAUCUCAGCUCACUGCAACCUCCGCCUCUUGGGUUCAAGCGAUUCUCCUGCCUCACCCUCCCGAGUAGCUGGGGCUACAGGCGCCCGCCACCACACCCAGCUAAUUUUUGUAUUUUUAAUAGAGACGGGGUUUCACCAUGUUGGCCAGGCUGGUCUCGAACUCCCAACCUCAGGUGAUCCCACAUCCUCAGCCUCCCAGAGUACUGGGAUUACAGGCGUGAAUCACUGCGCCUGGCCCAACCAGGCUAAUUUUUUUGUGUUUUUAGUAGAGACGGGGUUUCACCAUGUUAGCCAGGAUGGUUUCGAUCUCCUGACCUUGUGAUUCGCCCGCGUUGGCCUCCUAAAGUGCUGGUAUUACAGGCGUGAGCCACUGCGCCCGGCGGGGGAAACUUAUUCAAUGGUUGCACCGUCUCCUAAUUUGAGAGCCUUAUAUCAAGGAUGUAUAUUUAAUAUCUUACUUAAAUGAUUUUUUUUGGGUUCCUAUUUACUUCAGCAAAUACAUUGUAUAGGUAGCUUCUACUCAGCUUCAUUGGGUUUAUUGUGGGGGCAGUAUUUUGGUCUUGCCCUAAGCCAAAGUCCACCGGACUGUAGCGGGAUGACUCCAAAUAACUCUUAUCCCAUCGCUCCCUCAAACAUCUACAUAAUAGUCUCCAGUCUGUGACUUAGAAUUUCACCUCCUCUGGAUACUUCCCUCAGUGUUUCUGCAUAAUUUACUUGUUGACCUCAUUACAUCUUGUAGCACUAUGGAUCACCCACUGAAUGCAUGAGAAGAAAUAAAGGGGAUAUCAAGGAGUUUUGGCCUCAACAGUCCCAGCUAUCUGACUUCAUGUGAAAGAUGGCUAAUGCAGAAGUGAGUGUCCCAGUGGGGGAUGUGGUUGUGGUACCUACUGAAGGAAAUGAAGGGGAGAAUCCUGAAGACACUAAAACCCAAGUGAUUUUGCAGUUACAGCCUGUGCAACAAGGUUUGUUUAUCGAUGGACACUUUUACAACAGGAUUUAUGAAGCUGGGUCGGAGAACAACACGGCAGUUGUAGCAGUAGAAACUCACACGAUACACAAAAUUGAAGAAGGGAUUGAUACAGGCACUAUAGAAGCAAAUGAGGAUAUGGAAAUUGCUUACCCCAUAACUUGUGGGGAGAGCAAAGCCAUCCUCCUCUGGAAGAAGUUUGUAUGUCCAGGAAUAAACGUGAAGUGUGUCAAGUUCAAUGAUCAGUUGAUCAGCCCCAAGCACUUUGUUCAUCUGGCUGGCAAGUCCACUCUGAAGGACUGGAAGAGAGCUAUUCGUCUGGGUGGGAUCAUGCUCAGGAAAAUGAUGGACUCCGGACAGAUUGAUUUUUACCAACAUGACAAAGUUUGCUCCAAUACCUGCAGAAGCACCAAAUUUGAUCUUCUGAUCAGCAGUGCAAGAGCUCCAGUGCCAGGACAGCAGACAAGUGUGGUGCAGACACCCACUUCGGCUGAUGGUAGCAUCACGCAGAUUGCCAUCUCAGAAGAGAGCAUGGAAGAGGCAGGGCUGGAAUGGAACUCAGCUCUCACCGCUGCUGUCACCAUGGCCACGGAGGAGGGUGUAAAGAAAGACUCAGAGGAAAUUUCAGAGGACACUUUGAUGUUCUGGAAAGGAAUAGCUGAUGUAGGGCUGAUGGAAGAGGUUGUCUGCAAUAUACAGAAGGAAAUAGAGGAGCUACUCAGGGGAGUUCAGCAGCGGCUCAUCCAGGCUCCCUUCCAAGUCACAGAUGCUGCUGUUCUCAACAAUGUAGCACACACAUUUGGCCUAAUGGACACAGUCAAGAAGGUUUUAGACAACAGAAGGAACCAAGUAGAGCAGGGAGAAGAACAGUUUCUCUAUACUCUGACAGACUUGGAACGCCAGUUGGAGGAGCAGAAGAAGCAAGGCCAGGAUCACAGGCUGAAAUCUCAGACAGUUCAAAAUGUGGUACUGAUGCCUGUGAGCACUCCUAAGCCUCCAAAAAGGCCCCGGCUCCAGCGGCCAGCCUCCACCACUGUCUUGAGCCCUUCUCCUCCUGUCCAGCAGCCUCAGUUCACAGUCAUCUCACCCAUCACCAUCACCCCAGUGGGUCAGUCAUUUUCCAUGGGCAAUAUUCCAGUGGCCACCCUCAGCCAGGGCUCCAGUCCUGUGACUGUCCACACACUGCCUUCUGGCCCUCAGCUCUUCCGCUAUGCCACAGUGGUCUCCUCUGCCAAGAGCAGCUCACCAGACACAGUGACCAUCCACCCUUCAUCUAGCUUGGCGCUGCUGAGCUCUACUGCCAUGCAGGAUGGGAGUACACUGGGCAACAUGACCACCAUGGUUAGCCCUGUGGAAUUGGUGGCCAUGGAGUCCGGCCUAACCUCGGCAAUUCAGGCUGUUGAAAGCACCUCAGAGGAUGGGCAGACCAUCAUUGAGAUUGAUCCAGCCCCGGACCCAGAAGCUGAAGAUACUGAGGGCAAAGCAGUCAUCUUGGAGACAGAGCUGAGGACUGAGGAGAAAGUUGUGGCUGAGAUGGAAGAACACCAGCAUCAAGUUCACAAUGUGGAGAUUGUGGUCUUAGAGGAUUAACUGGGGAUCUCAGGGCCAGGAGUUAUGUUUUGAUUUGGAAUUUUAAUUAUUUGUUUAUUUUUAUCAUUGUCCCACUCAUUUCCACAUAGGACCCUUUUUUAAAAAAAAAAAAACAAAAUCUUAUUGUUGUAACUGAAAAUGUUGGGUUCUUCCCACUCCCUCAUUGAAAAAUGGACAAAACAAGCUGCCCUUCCAGAAGUUGAGAGUAGGUCAUUCAAUGUCCUAAUCAUCUUACACCAAGAAAGUAAUUUCUUUUAGGGGAAGUGUCAAGAUAACAAGUAACCCUGUCCAGAAAGCCAUUUCCAGGCUCGUCUGUGUGUGUAGGCAUGUGGUUUUAUUCUUGUAAAGAUGCAUUGACCAAACUCUGGAACACAGAUCUGACACUGGAAGGCAACCCACUCGCAUGUGGAUGCUGAAGGGCACUUUAUUUUGUAUCCUGAAAAGGGCCUACAGAGGCCAGUACAAAACUCUCAAACAAAAGGAAGUUGACUCUGCUUUGAGGGGAAGGUGGCAUGCCAGCACUAGCUUAAAAAGGGAAGUGCUAGCCGGGCGUGGUGGCUCACGCCUGCAAUCCCAGCACUUUGGGAGGCCGAGGCGGGUGGAUCACGAGGUCAGGAGUUUGAGACCAGCCUGGCCAACAUGGUGAAACCCCGUAUCUACUAAAAAUACGAAAAAAAAAUUAGCCGGGUGUGGUGGCGGGAGCCUGUAAUCCCAGCUAUUCAGGAGGCCAAGGCAGGAGAAUCGCUUGAACCUGGGAAGGCAGAGGUUGCAGUGAGCCAAGAUCGCACCACUGCACUCCAGCCUGGGCAACAAGAGCGAGACUCCAUCUCAAAAAAAAAAAAAAAAAAAAGUGCUUUGGCAAGUAUGGGGCAGGGAAAUCAUCUUACUUCCAGAGGUGCAACUGACGCCUCUGGAGAUCUCCAAAAGUUAGUACCGUGAGUGCCAUUUUGAGAAGAAGGUGGUAAUAAGUGGAAGGUACAUCUCCACAGAGCAAGUGGCAGCAGUGGCCUGUGGUUUUGCAGAAAUGGAAAGCCAAGGCCGGGUGCGGUGGCUCAUGCCUGUAAUCCCAGCACUUUGGGAGGCCGAGGUGGGUGAAUCACCUGAGGUCAGGAGUUUGAGGCCAGCCUGGCCAACAUGGUGAAACCCCGUCUCUACUGAAAAUACAAAAAAAAAAAAUUAGCUGGGCAUGGUGGCACGCGCCUGUAAUCCCAGCUACUUGGGAGGCUGAGGCAGGAGAAUUGCUUGAACCUGGGAGGCGGAGGUUGCAGUGAGCUGAGAUCAUGCCAUUGCACUCUAGCCUGGGCGAGGAGUGAAACUCCGUCUCAAAAAAAAAGAAAGAAAUGGAAAGCCAAGGAUGCUGCAGCUGUGCUUUGGGGUUCAAGGUAAUAGCUUACCUUGUUCCACACUUUGUCAAAGCACUCACCCUCCUAAGCUAGGACCAGUCCAUUCAUUUGAAACUGUGCAAUGUGAUGUAAAUGGCUCUGGUUCUUAGACUGUGGCUGUCACAGGGAUGGGGCUCCAAGGCCAUCAUUUUCAUUGCAUGGCUCCAAGAGCAGGGAGUUCCUCAAUGAAACCAGCUGCCUUUUUUGGUGGGGCCAUUUUUUUGGCUUUGGAACCCAAAGCAGCCACUCAUUUGGUGCUUCCUCUUGUUCUGCCCUCCAUCCCUCAACUCUUAAUGGCAUCUGUCUCCUAGAACCCACGCUCUUCAGCUUUUUGGCUGAUUUGGAGAACAGUGACAGGUGCCUGCCUGCCUUCGUCCCCUUUUAGAUUCAUUUAUACCACAGAUGUUUCUGUGAGAUACUGAGAUCAUAAAAAGCUUUAGGCUUGGCAGAGAGGACUCAACACCCCCAGGCUUUCCUGAGGCACCAACUAGAUGUCUCUUGAGUGAGCUGGACUCCCUGGGAAAGAAGCAUUGUCUGCAACAUUAUAUUAUAGGAAAUGUACCAGGAAUGUCAAUAAUAAUGCUUUGGGGGGGGGGGUUAUUUUGUUUUGUUUUGUUUUUAAUGUUGUUUGUAUAUUUAGAGCUGGGCCAUUUUCCGUGCUGCGAUUUCUUCUCUUUGACCCUCUUCAGUGUUUGGGGCAAGAGUGGACCCUGGUUUUUAUUUCUUUGAUUGCAUUGUUUACUGCACUAGGAAAAAUAUAGAGAUACAGGGAAACUACAGACAAAUUUAAGGAAAAAUAGGUCAAAAAAGAAAGCACACACCUUAAGAGUGGGAGGAAUAUUUUUAUUAAAAACAAAACUUGGACCUGUAGUUUUUUUUUUUCUUUUUUAUUUUUAAGAAGGCACCUUUCAGAAGCCAUGUUUCUUCCAACAGAUGUUGGAAACCCCAUCGAGCAAGUAAAAGUUGCAUUCUCCAUCCCUCAGAUGGCUGUAUGUAGUCAAAGAAACCCUGUAACAUGGUAAGGUUGCUGUUUUUUUUUUUUUUUUCUUUUUGAGAUGGAGUCUUGCUCUGUAGCCCAGGCUGGAGUGCAAUGGUGUGAUCUCAGCUCACUGCAACCUCCGCCUCCUUGGUUCAAGUGAUUCUCCUGCCUCAGCCUCCUGAGUAGCUGGGAUUACAGGCUCCCACCACCACGCCCGGGUAAUUUUUGUAUUUUUAGUAGAGACGGGGUUUUGCCAUGUUGGCCAGGCUGGUCUUGAACUCCUGACCUCAAGCGAUCCGCCCGCCUUGGCCUCCCAAAGUGUUGGGAUUACAGGCAUGAGCCACCGCACCCAGCCUGAAGGUGACUCUUAAGAAUGAGAUUUAUGAACUCCAUACAGUUGUAGAUUUCAGUUUUUAAAUAGUCUGGGGUUUUAUUUUUCUUUUCAAAAUAUCUAAUAGACUUAGCAAUCAAUUUAGAACAAAUAUUUGGCCCUUAAUAUAUCUUUAGUGAGGGAAGUAGCUUUUAUUUCCUGCUUGUUUAGGUUUUCUGUUGGUACAUAAAAACAAAAUUGCUGUCUCAGACUGAAUCUACUUGAAUCUAGGAAGGCACAUCUCAUCCCUAUUGUGGUUUUUAGGGACACUUUUCUCUUUCCCAGAGAUGAGAGGACCAAUUCAGGACAGAAGAGCCCUCGUGAAUACCAACGUGCUAGCUCAGGUUCCCUUCUUUCCUCCAUCAGAGCUAUUGGUAGGGUUUUAAGGUCGUGUGUGCAUCAUGCUUCCAAUGUCAAGAGAUUUCCUCAAACAGCCUGUUUACUAGAUGAAUUUUCCAGCUGGUGAAAUACAUGAGCUUUGUUGUUUUCCUGGUCUUCCAAUAGCCUGUCAUUAUUGUUAGAUAUUAUGGCACCUGUUGUUGAAUGUAGGUUCCCUUACAGCCCUGGUCUAGAUGAUCCUAGAUGGGGUGAGACAUAUGCAAGCCAUUGGUAUGUGCAUAAGCAGUUGCAAUGAACCUUAGGCUGACUUGGUAGUAGGCAUUUGUCUUUCUGUUCAUGCAUUGAAUAAACAUUUUUAAGAACCAUCUAUGUGCCAGGCUUUGUGCUAGGCACUGACAGUAGAGAGAUGAAGACAUAGUCCUUGCACUUAAGGAAUUCAUACUCCAGAUGUCUGGAGUUAAGAAAUACAUAUUUCAGCCAGGCAUGGUGGCUCACACCUAGAAUCCCAGCACUUUCAGAAGCUGAGGCAGAAUUGCUUGAGGCCAAGAGUUUAAGACUAGCCUGGUCAACAUAGCCAGACCCCAUCUCUAUAAAAAAAUGUAAAAAUUAGUCAAGUCUUGUGGCUCGCACUUGUAGACACAAUUACUCAGGAUGCUGAGGCAAGAGGAUUUUGCUUGGGCCUAGGAGUUCAAGGCUGUAGUGAGCUAUGACUUUGCCACUGUACUCUAGCCCAGGUAACAGGGCAACAUCCCCAGCUCAGAAAACCAAAACUACACAUUUCAUUAUAAUUGUUUUUUUUUGUAAUUUUAUGUAUUUUAUGCAUUGAAAAACAUUAUUUAAGAAUUGGUUCAUAGGUUUCAGCAGACUGCCAAAGGCACAAACAAGCAGCUCUCCUUUACUGAGGUACUGAAACAGAUCCUACUGCGUAAGUGCUGUGUGUGAUAGGGCUAUUGGCUAGGAGCUGAGAGAACAAAGCAUGAAGUGCCUAACCCAGCUUAGCGGUGUAGAGGUGGGGUCAGCAAAUAAGGGAGAUCUUCCUGGAGAAGGCAUAUACCUAAGCUGAUUUAGGAGAGACCACUUUUGGCUAGGUUUAUUGUACUACUUGAUUUUCAAGUAAUUGGGCUUAUUUAUUCUAGAGAAAAAGUCUUCAGUCUCUUGCUUCUGCCUGCAAAGCAAGGCAGAGUCAGCAACAUGGGCAGUCUCCCCACUGGAGAACGCUGAGUCAUGCAUGGGCUUCUCCAAGUUUCCAUCAGAUGGGAUCCAGUGUUGAAUCCAGUGCAGGACUGGAGUCUAGCUGGCAAAGGGUAAAUGCCCCCAAAGCCUUCCUGCCAUAUGGUUUCCACGAAGGCCUGAGAGUCAGCUGUACAACUGUCUUGUCUUGGCCAUGUCCCUGUUUGGUCCCUGCCUUGUUCUCUUCCCUUUCUCAAUUUCCAAGCUCCACCCACUCCUAAAAACACCAGUCAUUCUGAAGUAAAAAAUGGACAAUAAACAUGAAUAUUCAAGAUUCAAA